AUUCCACCUUCUGAAGCUUCUGUCGAACCAGUUGUAAGGAGAAUGGAGAGAGCAGUGAGAGUGGAGUCCGGGGUCCUGGUCGGGGUGGUCUGUCUGCUCCUGGCAUGCCCUGCCACAGCCACUGGGCCCGAAGUUGCUCAGCCUGAAGUAGACACCACCCUGGGUCGUGUGCGAGGCCGGCAGGUGGGCGUGAAGGGCACAGACCGCCUUGUGAAUGUCUUUCUGGGCAUUCCAUUUGCCCAGCCGCCACUGGGCCCUGACCGGUUCUCAGCCCCACACCCAGCACAGCCCUGGGAGGGUGUGCGGGAUGCCAGCACUGCGCCCCCAAUGUGCCUACAAGACGUGGAGAGCAUGAACAGCAGCAGAUUUGUCCUCAACGGAAAACAGCAGAUCUUCUCCGUUUCAGAGGACUGCCUGGUCCUCAACGUCUAUAGCCCAGCUGAGGUCCCCGCAGGGUCCGGUAGGCCGGUCAUGGUAUGGGUCCAUGGAGGCGCUCUGAUAACUGGCGCUGCCACCUCCUACGAUGGAUCAGCUCUGGCUGCCUAUGGGGAUGUGGUCGUGGUUACAGUCCAGUACCGCCUUGGGGUCCUUGGCUUCUUCAGCACUGGAGAUGAGCAUGCACCUGGCAACCAGGGCUUCCUAGAUGUGGUAGCUGCUUUGCGCUGGGUGCAAGAAAACAUCGCCCCCUUCGGGGGUGACCUCAACUGUGUCACUGUCUUUGGUGGAUCUGCCGGUGGGAGCAUCAUCUCUGGCCUGGUCCUGUCCCCAGUGGCUGCAGGGCUGUUCCACAGAGCCAUCACACAGAGUGGGGUCAUCACCACCCCAGGGAUCAUCGACUCUCACCCUUGGCCCCUAGCUCAGAAAAUCGCAAACACCUUGGCCUGCAGCUCCAGCUCCCCGGCUGAGAUGGUGCAGUGCCUUCAGCAGAAAGAAGGAGAAGAGCUGGUCCUUAGCAAGAAGCUGAAAAAUACUAUCUAUCCUCUCACCGUUGAUGGCACUGUCUUCCCCAAAAGCCCCAAGGAACUCCUGAAGGAGAAGCCCUUCCACUCUGUGCCCUUCCUCAUGGGUGUCAACAACCAUGAGUUCAGCUGGCUCAUCCCCAGGGGCUGGGGUCUCCUGGAUACAAUGGAGCAGAUGAGCCGGGAGGACAUGCUGGCCAUCUCAACACCCGUCUUGACCAGUCUGGAUGUGCCCCCUGAGAUGAUGCCCACCGUCAUAGAUGAAUACCUAGGAAGCAACUCGGACGCACAAGCCAAAUGCCAGGCGUUCCAGGAAUUCAUGGGUGACGUAUUCAUCAAUGUUCCCACCGUCAGUUUUUCAAGAUACCUUCGAGAUUCUGGAAGCCCUGUCUUUUUCUAUGAGUUCCAGCAUCGACCCAGUUCUUUUGCGAAGAUCAAACCUGCCUGGGUGAAGGCUGAUCAUGGGGCCGAGGGUGCUUUUGUGUUCGGAGGUCCCUUCCUCAUGGACGAGAGCUCCCGCCUGGCCUUUCCAGAGGCCACAGAGGAGGAGAAGCAGCUAAGCCUCACCAUGAUGGCCCAGUGGACCCACUUUGCCCGGACAGGGGACCCCAAUAGCAAGGCUCUGCCUCCUUGGCCCCAAUUCAACCAGGCGGAACAAUAUCUGGAGAUCAACCCAGUGCCACGGGCCGGACAGAAGUUCAGGGAGGCCUGGAUGCAGUUCUGGUCAGAGACGCUCCCCAGCAAGAUACAACAGUGGCACCAGAAGCAGAAGAACAGGAAGGCCCAGGAGGACCUCUGAGGCCAGGCCUGAACCUUCUUGGCUGGGGCAAACCACUCUUCAAGUGGUGGCAGAGUCCCAGCACGGCAGCCCGCCUCUCCCCCUGCUGAGACUUUAAUCUCCACCAGCCCUUAAAGUGUCGGCCGCUCUGUGACUGGAGUUAUGCUCUUUUGAAAUGUCACAAGGCCGCCUCCCACCUCUGGGGCAUUGUACAAGUUCUUCCCUCUCCCUGAAGUGCCUUUCCUGCUUUCUUCGUGGUAGGUUCUAGCACAUUCCUCUAGCUUCCUGGAGGACUCACUCCCCCAGGAAGCCUUCCCUGCCUUCUCUGGGCUGUGCGGCCCCGAGUCUGCGUCCAUUAGAGCACAGUCCACCCGAGGCUAGCACCGUGUCUGUGUCUGUCUCCCCCUCAGAGGAGCUCUCUCAAAAUGGGGAUUAGCCUAACCCCACUCUGUCACCCACACCAGGAUCGGGUGGGACCUGGAGCUAGGGGGUGUUUGCUGAGUGAGUGAGUGAAACACAGAAUAUGGGAAUGGCAGCUGCUGAACUUGAACCCAGAGCCUUCAGGUGCCAAAGCCAUACUCAGGCCCCCACCGACAUUGUCCACCCUGGCCAGAAGGGUGCAUGCCAAUGGCAGAGACCUGGGAUGGGAGAAGUCCUGGGGCGCCAGGGGAUCCAGCCUAGAGCAGACCUUAGCCCCUGACUAAGGCCUCAGACUAGGGCGGGAGGGGUCUCCUCCUCUCUGCUGCCCAGUCCUGGCCCCUGCACAAGACAACAGAAUCCAUCAGGGCCAUGAGUGUCACCCAGACCUGACCCUCACCAAUUCCAGCCCUGACCCUCAGGACGCUGGAUGCCAGCUCCCAGCCCCAGUGCCGGGUCCUCCCUCCCUUCCUGGCUUGGGGAGACCAGUUUCUGGGGAGCUUCCAAGAGCACCCACCAAGACACAGCAGGACAGGCCAGGGGAGGGCAUCUGGACCAGGGCAUCCGUCGGGCUAUUGUCACAGAGAAAAGAAGAGACCCACCCACUCGGGCUGCAAAAGGUGAAAAGCACCAAGAGGUUUUCAGAUGGAAGUGAGAGGUGACAGUGUGCUGGCAGCCCUCACAGCCCUCGCUUGCUCUCCCUGCCGCCUCUGCCUGGGCUCCCACUUUGGCAGCACUUGAGGAGCCCUUCAACCCGCCGCUGCACUGUAGGAGCCCCUUUCUGGGCUGGCCAAGGCCGGAGCCAGCUCCCUCAGCUUGCGGGGAGGUGCGGAGGGAGAGGGGCGGGCAGGAACCGGGGCUGCGCGCAGCGCUUGCGGGCCAGAGUGAGUUCCGGGUGGGCGUGGGCUCGGCGGGGCCCCACUCAGAGCAGCUGGCCGGCCCCAGGCAGUGAGGGCCUUAGCACCUGGGCCAGCAGCUGCUGUGCUCGAUUUCUCGCUGGGCCUUAGCUGCCUCCCCGCGGGGCAGGGCUCGGGACCUGCAGCCCUCCAUGCCUGACCCUCCCCCCACCCCCCGUGGGCUCCUGUGCGGCCGGAGCCUCCCCAAGGAGCGCCGCCCCCUGCUCCACAGCGCCCAGUCCCAUCGACCACCCAAGGGCUGAGGAGUGCGGGUGCACAGCGCGGGACUGGCAGGCAGCUCCACCUGCUGCCCCAGUGCUGGAUCCACUGGGUGAAGCCAGCUGGGCUCCUGAGUCUGGUGGGGACUUGGAGAACCUUUAUGUCUAGCUAAGGGAUUGUAAAUACACCGAUGGGCACUCUGUAUCUAGCUCAAGGUUUGUAAACACACCAAUCAGCACCCUGUGUCUAGCUCAGUGUUUGUGAAUGCACCAAUCCACACUCUGUAUCUGGCUACUCUGGUGGGGACUUGGAGAACCUUUGUGUCCACACUCUGUAUCUAGCUAAUCUAGUGGGGAUGUGGAGAACCUUUGUGUCUAGCUCAGGGAUCGUAAACGCACCAAUCAGCACCCUGUCAAAACAGACCACUUGACUCUCUGUAAAAUGGACCAAUCAGCAGGAUGUGGGUGGGGCGAGACAAGAGAAUAAAAGCAGGCUGCCUGAGCCAGCAGUGACAACCCCCCUCGGGUCCCCUCCCACGCCGUGGAAGCUUUGUUCUUUCGCUCUUUGCAAUAAAUCUUGCUACUGCCCA